ACUGCUUGAGCCGCUGAGAGGGUGGCGACGUCGGGGCCAUGGGGCUGGGCCCGGUCUUUCUGCUUCUGGCUGGCAUCUUCCCUUUUGCACCUCCGGGAGCUGCUGCUGAGCCCCACAGUCUUCGUUAUAACCUCACGGUGCUGUCCUGGGAUGGAUCUGUGCAGUCAGGGUUUCUUGCUGAGGUACAUCUGGAUGGUCAGCCCUUCCUGCGCUAUGACAGGCAGAAAUGCAGGGCAAAGCCCCAGGGACAGUGGGCAGAAGAUGUCCUGGGAAAUAAGACAUGGGACAGAGAGACCAGGGACUUGACAGGGAACGGAAAGGACCUCAGGAUGACCCUGGCUCAUAUCAAGGACCAGAAAGAAGGCUUGCAUUCCCUCCAGGAGAUUAGGGUCUGUGAGAUCCAUGAAGACAACAGCACCAGGAGCUCCCAGCAUUUCUACUACGAUGGGGAGCUCUUCCUCUCCCAAAACCUGGAGACUGAGGAAUGGACAGUGCCCCAGUCCUCCAGAGCUCAGACCUUGGCCAUGAACGUCAGGAAUUUCUUGAAGGAAGAUGCCAUGAAGACCAAGACACACUAUCACGCUAUGCAUGCAGACUGCCUGCAGGAACUACGGCGAUAUCUAGAAUCCGGCGUAGUCCUGAGGAGAACAGUGCCCCCCAUGGUGAAUGUCACCCGCAGCGAGGCCUCAGAGGGCAACAUCACCGUGACAUGCAGGGCUUCCAGCUUCUAUCCCCGGAAUAUCAUACUGACCUGGCGUCAGGAUGGGGUAUCUUUGAGCCACGACACCCAGCAGUGGGGGGAUGUCCUGCCUGAUGGGAAUGGAACCUACCAGACCUGGGUGGCCACCAGGAUUUGCCGAGGAGAGGAGCAGAGGUUCACCUGCUACAUGGAACACAGCGGGAAUCACAGCACUCACCCUGUGCCCUCUGGGAAAGUGCUGGUGCUUCAGAGUCAUUGGCAGACAUUCCAUGUUUCUGCUGUUGCUGCUGGCUGCUGCUAUUUUUGUUAUUAUUAUUUUCUAUGUCCGUUGUUGUAAGAAGAAAACAUCAGCUGCAGAGGGUCCAGAGCUCGUGAGCCUGCAGGUCCUGGAUCAACACCCAGUUGGGACGAGUGACCACAGGGAUGCCACACAGCUCGGAUUUCAGCCUCUGAUGUCAGCUCUUGGGUCCACUGGCUCCACUGAGGGCACCUAGACUCUACAGCCAGGCGGCUGGAAUUGAAUUCCCUGCCUGGAUCUCACAAGCACUUUCCCUCUUGGUGCCUCAGUUUCCUGACCUAUGAAACAGAGAAAAUAAAAGCACUUAUUUAUUGUUGUUGGAGGCUGCAAAAUGUUAGUAGAUAUGAGGCAUUUGCAGCUGUGCCAUAUUAA